GGGGUUGACGAUGGCUGUGUUGUUGAAGGGCCUGUAGCCGGGGGGUUCCUGGCCGGAUCCCGGUCUACCCUUAGCCCAGACUCGUUCCGGACCCCAGCCCGGCCCGGAACACUCUGGGCGAGACGGCGGUGGCAACUCUCCCCUUGCCGCCAUGCACGACGCUUUCGAGCCAGUGCCGAUCCUAGAAAAGCUGCCUCUGCAAAUCGACUGUCUGGCUGCCUGGGAGGAAUGGCUUCUUGUGGGAACCAAACAAGGACAUCUUCUUCUCUAUAGGAUUCGGAAGGACGUUGUGCCAGCAGAUGUAGCAUCACCUGAAAGCGGCAGUUGCAACAGAUUUGAAGUGACACUAGAGAAAUCCAAUAAGAACUUCUCCAAAAAGAUUCAGCAGAUCCAUGUGGUUUCCCAGUUUAAGAUUCUGGUCAGCUUGUUAGAAAAUAACAUUUAUGUCCAUGACCUAUUGACAUUUCAACAAAUCACUACGGUUUCAAAGGCAAAGGGAGCAUCACUGUUUACUUGUGACCUCCAGCACACAGAGACCGGUGAGGAGGUGUUACGGAUGUGUGUGGCAGUAAAAAAGAAGCUGCAGCUCUAUUUCUGGAAGGACAGGGAAUUUCAUGAAUUGCAGGGGGACUUUAGUGUGCCAGAUGUGCCCAAGUCCAUGGCGUGGUGUGAAAAUUCUAUCUGUGUGGGUUUCAAGAGAGACUACUACCUAAUAAGGGUGGAUGGAAAGGGGUCCAUCAAAGAGCUCUUUCCAACAGGAAAACAGCUGGAGCCCUUAGUUGCACCUCUGGCAGAUGGAAAAGUGGCUGUGGGCCAGGAUGAUCUCACCGUGGUACUCAAUGAGGAAGGGAUCUGCACACAGAAAUGUGCCCUGAACUGGACGGACAUACCAGUGGCCAUGGAGCACCAGCCUCCCUACAUCAUUGCAGUGUUGCCUCGAUAUGUUGAGAUCCGAACAUUUGAACCGAGGCUUCUGGUCCAAAGCAUUGAAUUGCAAAGGCCCCGUUUCAUUACCUCAGGAGGAUCAAACAUUAUCUAUGUGGCCAGCAAUCAUUUUGUUUGGAGACUCAUCCCUGUCCCCAUGGCAACCCAAAUCCAACAACUUCUCCAGGACAAGCAGUUUGAAUUGGCUCUGCAGCUCGCAGAAAUGAAAGAUGAUUCUGACAGUGAAAAGCAGCAACAAAUUCAUCACAUCAAGAACUUGUAUGCCUUCAACCUCUUCUGCCAGAAGCGUUUUGAUGAGUCCAUGCAGGUCUUUGCUAAACUUGGCACAGAUCCCACCCAUGUGAUGGGCCUGUACCCUGACCUGCUGCCCACAGACUACAGAAAGCAGUUGCAGUAUCCCAACCCAUUGCCUGUGCUCUCCGGGGCUGAAUUGGAGAAGGCUCACUUAGCUCUGAUUGACUACCUGACACAGAAACGAAGUCAAUUGGUAAAGAAGCUGAAUGACUCUGAUCACCAGUCAAGCACCUCACCGCUCAUGGAAGGCACUCCCACCAUCAAAUCCAAGAAGAAGCUGCUACAAAUCAUCGACACCACCCUGCUCAAGUGCUAUCUCCAUACAAAUGUGGCCCUGGUGGCCCCCUUGCUACGCCUGGAGAACAAUCACUGCCACAUCGAGGAGAGCGAGCACGUGCUAAAGAAGGCUCACAAGUACAGUGAGCUUAUCAUCCUGUAUGAGAAGAAGGGGCUCCACGAGAAAGCUCUGCAGGUGCUCGUGGACCAGUCCAAGAAAGCCAACUCCCCUCUGAAAGGCCACGAGAGGACAGUGCAGUAUCUGCAGCAUCUGGGCACAGAAAACCUGCAUUUGAUUUUCUCCUACUCAGUGUGGGUGCUGAGAGACUUCCCAGAAGAUGGCCUGAAGAUAUUUACUGAAGAUCUCCCGGAAGUGGAGUCUCUGCCACGUGAUCGAGUCCUCGGCUUCUUAAUAGAGAAUUUUAAGGGUCUGGCUAUUCCUUAUCUGGAACACAUCAUCCAUGUUUGGGAGGAGACAGGCUCUCGGUUCCACAACUGCCUGAUCCAGCUAUACUGUGAGAAGGUGCAAGGUCUGAUGAAGGAGUAUCUCCUGUCCUUCCCUGCAGGCAAAACCCCAGUCCCAGCUGGAGAGGAAGAGGGUGAGCUGGGAGAAUACCGGCAAAAGCUCCUCAUGUUCUUGGAGAUUUCCAGCUACUAUGAUCCAGGCCGGCUCAUCUGUGAUUUUCCCUUUGAUGGCCUCUUAGAAGAACGAGCUCUCCUGUUGGGGCGCAUGGGGAAACAUGAACAAGCUCUUUUCAUUUAUGUCCACAUCUUGAAGGAUACAAGGAUGGCUGAGGAGUACUGCCACAAACACUAUGACCGAAACAAAGAUGGCAACAAAGAUGUGUAUCUGUCCCUGCUUCGGAUGUACCUGUCGCCCCCCAGCAUUCACUGCCUGGGGCCAAUCAAGCUGGAACUACUGGAGCCAAAAGCCAACCUCCAGGCCGCUCUGCAGGUCCUCGAGCUACACCACAGCAAACUGGACACCACCAAGGCCCUCAACCUUCUGCCAGCAAACACUCAGAUCAAUGACAUACGCAUCUUCCUGGAAAAGGUCUUGGAAGAAAAUGCACAAAAGAAACGGUUCAAUCAAGUGCUCAAGAACCUUCUCCAUGCAGAAUUCCUGAGGGUCCAGGAAGAGCGGAUUUUACACCAGCAGGUGAAGUGCAUCAUCACAGAGGAGAAGGUGUGCAUGGUGUGUAAGAAGAAGAUUGGGAACAGGAGGUGCCGCUGCCAGAGAAGUGGUCACUUAGAAGCAGUCCUCACUCCCAAGCCAUUUUCUUCCCUGCAGUGCAUUUGCAAGAUACCCCAAUGGAGUGGUCGUCCAUUACUUCUGUUCCAAAGAGGUAAACCCAGCUGACACUUGAGCCCAGCAUCCUGGGGAUCCAGCGGAUGGACAGCUUGGCUCUCCCAGAGAGGUGAAGGAGCACCUGGCCUUAGGAAUCCUGGCUGCCACCACCACAAGGCUCCCCAUUUGGACAUUACUGGCUAUCUUGUGCCCUGGAACAACUCUGAAUUAAUUAGACUCAUGGUCUGGCAUUGCCAGCUUUUUAAUGGGAAAAGAGAUUAGUUAUACCUUAUACCAUUAUGUUGUGGGCAAUUCCAGAGAAUUCAGUACCUGCUUGGUCAGGAGGAUGUGCACCAUCUUGCCUUUGCACACCAGUCACCUGAACAAGGAAACUUGUCACAAGUGUUUGUAACCAUGGGGUUGUUCAUCAAGGGCUUUUCUAUUAAGUACAUGACUUCACAAGGACCGCUCAGCAUGGCUCACUGGAGAGUUCCAUGAGAGAACAGCACUCAAGCUUCUGGCCGCAUGGACCCGAUGGCUCGCAUUCUGUGUAGUGUUUUACGUCUCCAUGGUAACUGUGCCCUGCACCCCUCGGUAGCCGCCCUGUUAGUUUUCAGUCUCCUUUUCUUUCUCACCAUUUAUCACUUCCCUCACUGCCCUACCCAGGCUUUCUCUCCCACUUCCCUGACUCUGGGAAUAACUAAUAUUUAAGCAAGGUAAGAUGAGAAGCAAGGGGUCUCAGUUCUAGGAAUACAGUGCUAGUUGAUUGUCAGGUAUGUUGUAAAUAGACCCUCUUUGGCCAUACACUCCAUGCCUAGAUGCCUCGGAGAGCAUCAUUCUCUGCCUAGGCAAGGCCCUGCAUCCCUUGCCUCAGGCCGGGCUGAGUGUGACUGCAGCUCCUGAGGAUGGGCCUGCCCUGUCUGGGGUAUGCGUGAUCCCUAGAUACAUGUUCCCACAGAGGUGCCUGCUCCGUCUUCGCUCACCAGACACUCAGGCAGGCUGGCUUAGUCUUUGUGCGUGGCGAUUUUGUGCUCUGGGCCCUUUCUCUUUUUCCAGCCAGUUUCCAUUCACUUGCCUUACAGCCUGCCCUGGCCGUCACUCCCCAGCUUUGUUCAGCAAUGGUGUGGUUGGAGAGUUGUGCUGGGAUAGCGCAGGAAGGUGGGUCCCGGCAACACGCAGGGGAUGAGUGGACCUGGAACUGACAAUGGCGUGCUGCCAAGUGUUCCUGAGAGGUGUUUAGGCACAGCAGAGGGGACGCGGGGGGCAAGAACAGCAGGACGCUGGUUUAAAAAUAACUCACCGCCAAACCUGUGGAGCAGUGUGGGGCAUCCUGCCAGAGGUGCACAGGCUGGAGUUUCAGGCACUGCAGGCUGAUGACACACAGGGAGAGUGGCCCUGCCUCCUGUCCUCCCCGGGGUUUUUGCAGACUCGAAGUCUCACUGCACCAGUGUCUUUGAUGGUGGUGAGGGUGGGUGAUGGUGCCCAGCACCAACAGUUUUAGUGGCCUGUCCUUGACCUGCCGUGGUCCUUUGUAAACUAUGGCUCCAUGCUGUGUGACAGAUCAACGUGCUGAUGGUAAGUAGACUAGGCUUCCCCAGGCAUGCCGUCCGUGGGGGCCUGAAGAGACAGUGAGUGCCAUUGGCCCCAUUCGCAGAUGUGGGAGACUCUGCUCAGGCCUGUGAGGCUGGGCAGCCCUUCACCAGAGUUCGGAGGAGCAGUGUGUGGCGCCACGUCCCGACUGGCCAUACCCACACAGAAGCAGUGCUGCCCGGGGCCUCAUCUGGGCCAGCUUGGACUCUGCUUCCUCCAGGAGCAGCAGGGAAGCUCUGGGCCACCUCCCUGGAUAGCAGGAACUUGACCUGCCAUGUGUGCCCUGCCUUCCUGGCCAGCUGUGCUUGUUAUCUUCCAUUCUCACAAACUGUCUUUGAAGCAAUAGAAUAAAGAAUGUGUGUUUUCUUUCCUGGUAUACAUACAUGAUCCCAUGCUCCCAAGCUCCAUUCUUCCUUCCCUCAACUCUCUGCCCUCCACAGAGCUAUGGAGAAGGCUGGAGAUGAAAGCUUUGUAGUGAGGACUGAUAAAGAUCUCAUCACUGCUCCUUAUAAUAAACCUAAUAAAGCAAGAAACCAAGCCUA